CUGGCUUUGUCUUUACAGAUGUGAAUUUCUUCGGAGUAAGAAAUCCUCAGAGGAAAUUACCCAGUAUAUUCAAAGCUACAAGGGAUUUGUUGACAUAACGGUAAUGUAUAACAGCAAUUUUUUUCUCAAGUUUUUGGAUUACCUGUAAGUGUCUGACUCAGAAGGGCAUAGGCAUUCUUUUUAUGUCAUGGGUUUGAUUUCUUUCUUCCUUUCUCCUUUCAUUCCCCUGGCUCCCAUCUUCAAAGUGAAAAAUAUCACAUUCACUUGCUGACCUAGAGCCUUUUUCUUUUUCCAGGGCUGGCUUCUGACGGGCUCUGCUUGCCUUCCUGAUAGUCUUCCCCUUUAUGAAUGAAGCCACUUGCCCCAGCUUCCCUCUGCUGCCCCUAUCUGCAGGCUUGCUAAGAUCUCCUGACCUAGGCGCUGUCACCCACAGUGGGCUGCAGAGCUGGCUCUUCCUAGCUGGCUAACUAUCCUGAAUCAGUAAAAAUUUCCUAGUGGAGAGUGAUGGGAAAUCGAAUCCAAACUGGCUUAAACAAAAAUGAGAAUUUAUUGAUUAACAUGACUCAGGAGACCAGAACUCUAUAGAGAACAUGGCCUGACAGUGGGGGAAGAGAGGUGUUUCCUCAAAAAGAAAUUGGGUGCAGCUUUCCCAGAAGAAUCAGUUGCUCAAUAUAUAAUACCCUGAUGAAUUUAGUUACCAUUCUAUGUCUCUUACUUCCUCAUUCUUCAAAGUACAUCUGUGAUAUUUAAAUGCAGGUCUGUUUUCAAGGUCAGUUUCCGGAAACAGUGACCCUGAGAAGGCUUCCUCCUGAGUAUGCAUAAACAUUCACAGCUUGCAUGCGUGUGUGUGUGUGUGUGUGUGUGUAUGUUUGCUUGCACUGCAUAAAAACAAUUGCAACAUCAACAGAAAUAAAAAUUAAAGGAAUAAUUCUCCUCCGACUCUGCCGUUCCAUCCAGUGAAACUCUUCAUUCUGGGGGAGAACAUUUUGUGAAUUCCUGGGUCCAGAGAGAAUUACCUAUGGCAUCAGCUUAUUGCAAUGACAGCAUCUUUGCUUACGAAGAACUACGGCUGGACUCUUUUAAGGACUGGCCCCGGGAAUCAGCUGUGGGAGUUGCAGCACUGGCCAAAGCAGGUCUUUUCUACACAGGUAUAAAGGACAUCGUCCAGUGCUUUUCCUGUGGAGGGUGUUUAGAGAAAUGGCAGGAAGGUGAUGACCCAUUAGACGAUCACACCAGAUGUUUUCCCAAUUGUCCAUUUCUCCAAAAUAUGAAGUCCUCUGCGGAAGUGACUCCAGACCUUCAGAGCCGUGGUGAACUUUGUGAAUUACUGGAAACCACAAGUGAAAGCAAUCUUGAAGAUUCAAUAGCAGUUGGUCCUAUAGUGCCAGAAAUGGCACAGGGUGAAGCCCAGUGGUUUCAAGAGGCAAAGAAUCUGAAUGAGCAGCUGAGAGCAGCUUAUACCAGCGCCAGUUUCCGCCACAUGUCUUUGCUUGAUAUCUCUUCCGAUCUGGCCACGGACCACUUGCUGGGCUGUGAUCUGUCUAUUGCUUCAAAACACAUCAGCAAACCUGUGCAAGAACCUCUGGUGCUGCCUGAGGUCUUUGGCAACUUGAACUCUGUCAUGUGUGUGGAGGGUGAAGCUGGAAGUGGAAAGACGGUCCUCCUGAAGAAAAUAGCUUUUCUGUGGGCAUCUGGAUGCUGUCCCCUGUUAAACAGGUUCCAGCUGGUUUUCUACCUCUCCCUUAGUUCCACCAGACCAGACGAGGGGCUGGCCAGUAUCAUCUGUGACCAGCUCCUAGAGAAAGAAGGAUCUGUUACUGAAAUGUGCAUGAGGAACAUUAUCCAGCAGUUAAAGAAUCAGGUCUUAUUCCUUUUAGAUGACUACAAAGAAAUAUGUUCAAUCCCUCAAGUCAUAGGAAAACUGAUUCAAAAAAACCACUUAUCCCGGACCUGCCUAUUGAUUGCUGUCCGUACAAACAGGGCCAGGGACAUCCGCCGAUACCUAGAGACCAUUCUAGAGAUCAAAGCAUUUCCCUUUUAUAAUACUGUCUGUAUAUUACGGAAGCUCUUUUCACAUAAUAUGACUCGUCUGCGAAAGUUUAUGGUUUACUUUGGAAAGAACCAAAGUUUGCAGAAGAUACAGAAAACUCCUCUCUUUGUGGCGGCGAUCUGUGCUCAUUGGUUUCAGUAUCCUUUUGACCCAUCCUUUGAUGAUGUGGCUGUUUUCAAGUCCUAUAUGGAACGCCUUUCCUUAAGGAACAAAGCGACAGCUGAAAUUCUCAAAGCAACUGUGUCCUCCUGUGGUGAGCUGGCCUUGAAAGGGUUUUUUUCAUGUUGCUUUGAGUUUAAUGAUGAUGAUCUCGCAGAAGCAGGGGUUGAUGAAGAUGAAGAUCUAACCAUGUGCUUGAUGAGCAAAUUUACAGCCCAGAGACUAAGACCAUUCUACCGGUUUUUAAGUCCUGCCUUCCAAGAAUUUCUUGCGGGGAUGAGGCUGAUUGAACUCCUGGAUUCAGAUAGGCAGGAACAUCAAGAUUUGGGACUGUAUCAUUUGAAACAAAUCAACUCACCCAUGAUGACUGUAAGCGCCUACAACAAUUUUUUGAACUAUGUCUCCAGCCUCCCUUCAACAAAAGCAGGGCCCAAAAUUGUGUCUCAUUUGCUCCAUUUAGUGGAUAACAAAGAGUCAUUGGAGAAUAUAUCUGAAAAUGAUGACUACUUAAAGCACCAGCCAGAAAUUUCACUGCAGAUGCAGUUACUUAGGGGAUUGUGGCAAAUUUGUCCACAAGCUUACUUUUCAAUGGUUUCAGAACAUUUACUGGUUCUUGCCCUGAAAACUGCUUAUCAAAGCAACACUGUUGCUGCGUGUUCUCCAUUUGUUUUGCAAUUCCUUCAAGGGAGAACACUGACUUUGGGUGCGCUUAACUUACAGUACUUUUUCGACCACCCAGAAAGCUUGUCAUUGUUGAGGAGCAUCCACUUCCCAAUACGAGGAAAUAAGACAUCACCCAGAGCACAUUUUUCAGUUCUGGAAACAUGUUUUGACAAAUCACAGGUGCCAACUAUAGAUCAGGACUAUGCUUCUGCCUUUGAACCUAUGAAUGAAUGGGAGCGAAAUUUAGCUGAAAAAGAGGAUAAUGUAAAGAGCUAUAUGGAUAUGCAGCGCAGGGCAUCACCAGACCUUAGUACUGGCUAUUGGAAACUUUCUCCAAAGCAGUACAAGAUUCCCUGUCUAGAAGUCGAUGUGAAUGAUAUUGAUGUUGUAGGCCAGGAUAUGCUUGAGAUUCUAAUGACAGUUUUCUCAGCUUCACAGCGCAUCGAACUCCAUUUAAACCACAGCAGAGGCUUUAUAGAAAGCAUCCGCCCAGCUCUUGAGCUGUCUAAGGCCUCUGUCACCAAGUGCUCCAUAAGCAAGUUGGAACUCAGCGCAGCCGAACAGGAACUGCUUCUCACCCUGCCUUCCCUGGAAUCUCUUGAAGUCUCAGGGACAAUCCAGUCACAAGACCAAAUCUUUCCUAAUCUGGAUAAGUUCCUGUGCCUGAAAGAACUGUCUGUGGAUCUGGAGGGCAAUAUAAAUGUUUUUUCAGUCAUUCCUGAAGAAUUUCCAAACUUCCACCAUAUGGAGAAAUUAUUGAUCCAAAUUUCAGCUGAGUAUGAUCCUUCCAAACUAGUAAAAUUAAUUCAAAAUUCUCCAAACCUUCAUGUUUUCCAUCUGAAGUGUAACUUCUUUUCGGAUUUUGGGUCUCUCAUGACUAUGCUUGUUUCCUGUAAGAAACUCACAGAAAUUAAGUUUUCGGAUUCAUUUUUUCAAGCCGUCCCAUUUGUUGCCAGUUUGCCAAAUUUUAUUUCUCUGAAGAUAUUAAAUCUUGAAGGCCAGCAAUUUCCUGAUGAGGAAACAUCAGAAAAAUUUGCCUACAUUUUAGGUUCUCUUAGUAACCUGGAAGAAUUGAUCCUUCCUACUGGGGAUGGAAUUUAUCGAGUGGCCAAACUGAUCAUCCAGCAGUGUCAGCAGCUUCAUUGUCUCCGAGUCCUCUCAUUUUUCAAGACUUUGAAUGAUGACAGCGUGGUGGAAAUUGCCAAAGUAGCAAUCAGUGGAGGUUUCCAGAAACUUGAGAACCUAAAGCUUUCAAUCAAUCACAAGAUUACAGAGGAAGGAUACAGAAAUUUCUUUCAAGCACUGGACAACAUGCCAAACUUGCAGGAGUUGGACAUCUCCAGGCAUUUCACAGAGUGUAUCAAAGCUCAGGCCACAACAGUCAAGUCUUUGAGUCAAUGUGUGUUACGACUACCAAGGCUCAUUAGACUGAACAUGUUAAGUUGGCUCUUGGAUGCAGAUGAUAUUGCAUUGCUUAAUGUCAUGAAAGAAAGACAUCCUCAAUCUAAGUACUUAACUAUUCUCCAGAAAUGGAUACUGCCGUUCUCUCCAAUCAUUCAGAAAUAAAAGAUUCAGCUAAAAACUGCUGAAUCAAUAAUUUGUCUUGGGGCAUAUUGAGGAUGUAAAAAAAGUUGUUGAUUAAUGCUAAAAACCAAAUUAUCCAAAAUUAUUUUAUUAAAUAUUGCAUACAAAAGAAAAUGUGUAAGGCUUGCUAAAAAACAAAACAAAACAAAACACAGUCCUGCAUACUCACCACCAAGCUCAAGAAAUAAAUCAUCACCAAUACCUUUGAGGUCCCUGAGUAAUCCACCCCAGCUAAAGGCAAACCCUUCAAUCAAGUUUAUACAGCAAACCCUCCAUUGUCCAUGGUCAACAGGGAAGGGGUUGGGGACAGGUCUGCCAAUCUAUCUAAAAGCCACAAUAUGGAAGAAGUAUUCAAUUUAUAUAAUAAAUGGCUAACUUAACGGUUGAAUCACUUUCAUACAUGGAUGAAACGGGUUUAACACAGGAUCCACAUGAAUCUUCUGUGGGCCAAGAGAUGUUCCUUAAUCCUUGUAGAACCUGUUUUCUAUAUUGAACUAGCUUUGGUACAGUAGAGUUAACUUACUUUCCAUUUAUCCACUGCCAAUAUAAAGAGGAAACAGGGGUUAGGGAAAAAUGACUUCAUUCCAGAGGCUUCUCAGAGUUCAACAUAUGCUAUAAUUUAGAAUUUUCUUAUGAAUCCACUCUACUUGGGUAGAAAAUAUUUUAUCUCUAGUGAUUGCAUAUUAUUUCCAUAUCAUAGUAUUUCAUAGUAUUAUAUUUGAUAUGAGUGUCUAUAUCAAUGUCAGUGUCCAGAAUUUCGUUCCUACCAGUUAAGUAGUUUUCUGAACGGCCAGAAGACCAUUCGAAAUUCAUGAUACUACUAUAAGUUGGUAAACAACCAUACUUUUAUCCUCAUUUUUAUUCUCACUAAGAAAAAAGUCAACUCCCCUCCCCUUGCCCAAGUAUGAAAUAUAGGGACAGUAUGUAUGGUGUGGUCUCAUUUGUUUAGAAAACCACUUAUGACUGGGUGCGGUGGCUCACACCUGUAAUCCCAGCACUUUGGGAGGCUGAGGCGGGCGAAUCAUUUGAGGUGAGGAAUUCGAGACCAGCCUGGCCAGCAUGGUGAAACCCCAUCUCUACUAAAAAUACAAAAAUUAGCCAGGUGUGGUGGCACAUGCCUGUAGUCCCAGCCACUAGGGCGGCUGAGACGCAAGACUUGCUUGAACCCGGGAGGCAGAGGUUGCAGUGAGCCAAGAUGGCGCCACUGCAUUCCAGCCUGGGCAACAGAGCAAGACCCUGUCUGUCUCAAAACAAAAAACAAAACCACUUAUAUUGCUAGCUACAUUAAGAAUUUCUGAAUAUGUUACUGAGCUUGCUUGUGGUAACCAUUUAUAAUAUCAGAAAGUAUAUGUACACCAAAA